GCUGGGAGGCGAAGACCAGGCGGGCACUGUUGCCCGGCGACGCUCCGGCGCUGGGUCCCCGAGGCCCGGCCCCUCCCCGGGAGGAGGUGGGCUUCGAGUCACGUGACCCGUGCCCUACGGGAGGGGGUGCGGUCGGGGACCCGGCAGGAGGCGGCCGAGAAGAGAGGACCGUGGGGGCGUUCGCGUGGCUCCCAGCCCGGGACCCCACCCCCGCUGGACAGUGGGGGAAACUGAGGCCUGAGCGGGCUGGAGUGCAAUGGCAAAUCUCGGCACACUACAACUUCUGCCUCCCAGGUUCAAGCGAUUCUCCUGCCUCAGCCUCCCAAAUAUCUGGAUUACAGGCAUGCCUGUGCCGGCCACCUCUGUCCCCUGUCCCUCUGCAGGCCCACACAGGACCAUGAAGGUGCUUCUCCUCACAGGGCUGGGGGCCCUGUUCUUCGCCUAUUAUUGGGAUGACAACUUCGACCCAGCCAGCCUCCAGGGAGCGCGAGUGCUGCUGACAGGGGCCAACGCUGGUGUUGGUGAGGAGCUGGCCUAUCACUACGCGCGUCUGGGCUCCCACCUGGUGCUCACUGCCCACACUGAGGCUCUCCUGCAGAAGGUGGUAGGGAACUGCCGGAAGCUGGGCGCCCCCAAGGUCUUCUACAUCGCGGCGGACAUGGCCUCCCCUGAGGCGCCCGAGAGCGUGGUGCAGUUUGCGCUGGACAAGCUGGGCGGGCUGGACUACCUCGUGCUGAACCACAUCGGCGGCGCCCCGGCCGGCACGCGAGCCCGCAGCCCCCAGGCAACUCGCUGGCUCAUGCAGGUAAACUUUGUGAGCUACGUGCAACUGACGUCGCGGGCGCUGCCCAGCCUGACGGACAGCAAGGGCUCCCUGGUGGUGGUGUCCUCGCUGCUCGGCCGCGUGCCCACGUCGUUCUCCACUCCCUACUCGGCGGCCAAGUUUGCGCUGGACGGCUUCUUCGGCUCCCUGCGGCGGGAGCUGGACGUGCAGGACGUGAACGUGGCCAUCACCAUGUGCGUCCUGGGCCUCCGAGAUCGCGCCUCCGCCGCCGAGGCAGUCAGGGGAGUCACGAGGGUCAAGGCGGCCCCGGGGCCCAAGGCAGCCCUGGCCGUGAUCCGCGGCGGCGCCACGCGCGCGGCCGGCGUCUUCUACCCGUGGCGUUUCCGCCUGCUGUGCUUGCUCCGGCGCUGGCUACCGCGCCCGCGGGCCUGGUUUAUCCGCCAGGAGCUCAACGUCACGGCCGCGGCAGCCUGAGCACCGGGGGGUGCCCCUCCAGUCCCAGACGGCAAUGUUCCUCCCUCCAACUGUCCCUGGAGCCAGAACACUCACAGAGACACCCCUGAGAGGGUGGCCACAGCCCAAGAUGAAGUCAUCAAGACAGAAAAGCAAAACCGAGAAAAACGACGGGCACCUGGAACCAGUCACGGCUUGGGAGGUGCAGGUGCCCCGUGUUAGGCGCCUUUGUCGGGGACUUGCAAGGCCUCACCUGUUUGGCCAUGAUUGAUGACGUGACUGCUUCCAUUUUGCAGAUGAGGAAACUAAGGCUCAGAGAGGCCACGCCACCCUUGAGCCACCCAUGGACCCCUCUCCAUCUCCUGCCUGCGCCUUUAAGUCCCUGAUUUAUUCUUUCCAUUCAUUCCAUCUGGGAGGAACCCCCCCAACUCCUGCCAGCUUCCCCUAGCUGGGGUCUCUGGUACUCUUCACACCUGCAGGGGCGUCUACACUGUUCGUCUACCUGGUGGCAGGGUCUGAGCGGGAGGAGGAGGGAAAGAGUGUGUUCUGAGCUGGACCCAGCCUCUUGUUCGAGAAUAAAAACUCUUCUUCUCUUGCA